ACACAGAGAGUCAGGGCCAGCCAAAUGGAAAUUGUCUGCUCAUAGGAGAAGCCCCGGGGCCAUACUCUGAAAGAGGUAGCUUGGCGACAGACAAAUUUUCUAAGAGAGACAGUAUGGGGAGAAGAAAAGGCAAAGGUCCAAGACUCAAAAAAUGAAUGAAUGUUAAAACAUCAGAAGAGCAAGAUAAACGAGUUAAGAAGAUGGCACAGGAGCCGCAGAGAGGUGGAAGAUGGCUUGGAAGAGUGAAAACAGUUUUGCUGAGGACAGAAGAGAUGAGGUGGGGAUGGUCCAUGAAGAUGAAUGACUGCUUCCUAAGACACUGUGGCGAGGAGGCUGUGGAAAGAUGGCAGCAGCAGACUGUGGAGAGAAGUCAAUUCACUGGCAGCUUGGCACUUCCCCAGGUAAUCCAUUCUCAGAGUUUCUGUUCAAUCAAAAACUGUAGCUUCUUUGGUUUAGGAGUUUCCUGAGCCUGUCUCAGGGCAAUAACGCCUUCUGGGUUAACUGGAGACUUCGUCAGAGACAGAUGGGAGCUAACUCCAAAGAGUCAUCAUGAUAACUGCGGUUGUUCAGAUUCUUUAUUUCUGGGCAUCACAUAGAAUUUAGAUUGGGACUCCUUUUCUAUCUAACUGAGGGAUGGGAAUCAUAAUUGCAUAUUUAAUUUUGUCAUUAGAAAUGAUAAUAAACUCAUUGCCAUUAUACCACAUGGUUUAAAAAUAAUCUGUUAGAGCAUUUGUUUCUUGUUGUUCAAUGUAACCAACCUUAUUAAAGACCUUGUAUCAACA